GAGUUUGGAGCAAGUAACUGUCAGUGAGGUUGCAGUUGGUCUGGGCUGUUUGGCUGUGAGCGAAAUAGCUGCCCCCCACUUCUCACUUGCACACCACGGGAUACUCCUCCUGAGGCUCCGGAUGAUUCAGAUGGACUGUGAAAAACAACAAGAUGGAUGAUCAUAUGGAGAUUGCUUCUAACAUAAAUCUGCAUAAAAAUUUUUCUGAAACAUGGCUGGAAUAUUUAAGGAGUUUUUUUUCAGUACUGAGGACCUCCCUGAAGUCAUUCUAACAUUGUCUUUGAUCAGCUCCAUUGGAGCAUUUUUGAACCGGCACUUGGAAGACUUUCCAAUUCCUGUCCCUGUGAUAUUAUUUUUACUUGGAUGCAGUUUUGAAGUAUUAAGCUUUACAUCUUCACAGGUCCAAAGAUACGCAAACGCCAUACAAUGGAUGAGUCCAGACUUAUUUUUUCGUAUAUUUACACCAGUAGUUUUCUUUACUACUGCAUUUGACAUGGAUACGUACAUGCUUCAAAAGUUAUUUUGGCAGAUACUUUUAAUUUCAAUUCCCGGCUUUUUGGUUAAUUAUAUCUUAGUUCUUUGGCAUCUGGCAUCUGUAAAUCAAUUACUUUUGAAGCCUACCCAAUGGUUAUUAUUUUCAGCUAUCCUUGUGAGUUCAGAUCCCAUGCUAACCGCAGCUGCUAUAAGAGACCUUGGGCUUUCUAGAAGCCUCAUCAGUUUAAUUAAUGGAGAAAGUCUGAUGACCUCUGUUAUAUCAUUAAUUACAUUUACUAGUAUUAUGGAUUUUGACCAAAGACUACAAAGUAAAAGAAACCAUACCUUAGCUGAAGAGAUCGUGGGUGGAAUUUGUUCAUAUAUUAUAGCAAGUUUCUUGUUUGGAAUUCUAAGUUCAAAACUGAUUCAAUUUUGGAUGUCAACUGUUUUUGGUGAUGAUGUCAAUCAUAUAAGUCUCAUCUUUUCAAUUCUGUAUCUCAUCUUUUAUAUUUGUGAGUUAGUUGGAAUGUCAGGAAUAUUUACUCUGGCCAUUGUGGGACUUCUUUUAAAUUCUACAAGUUUUAAAGCAGCAAUUGAAGAAACACUUCUUCUUGAAUUCUGGACUUUUCUAUCACGUAUUGCUUUUCUCAUGGUGUUUACUUUCUUUGGACUUCUAAUUCCUGCACAUACAUAUUUGUAUAUAGAAUUUGUUGAUAUAUACUAUUCAUUAAAUAUCUACUUAACAUUGAUUGUUUUAAGAUUUCUGACCCUUCUUUUAAUAAGCCCUGUUUUGUCUCGAGUUGGUCAUGAGUUCAGUUGGCGCUGGAUAUUCAUAAUGGUCUGUAGUGAAAUGAAGGGGAUGCCUAAUAUAAACAUGGCCCUUCUGCUUGCCUACUCUGAUCUUUAUUUUGGAUCUGACAAAGAAAAAUCUCAAAUAUUAUUUCAUGGAGUGUUAGUAUGCCUAAUAACCCUUGUUGUCAAUAGAUUUAUUUUGCCAGUGGCAGUUACUAUACUAGGUCUUCGUGAUGCCACAUCAACAAAAUAUAAAUCGGUUUGUUGCACAUUUCAACACUUUCAAGAGCUAACCAAGUCUGCAGCCUCUGCCCUUAAAUUUGACAAAGAUCUUGCUAAUGCUGAUUGGAACAUGAUUGAGAAAGCAAUUACACUUGAAAACCCAUACAUGUUGAACGAAGAAGAAACAACAGAACAUCAGAAGGUGAAAUGUCCACACUGUAACAAGGAAAUAGAUGAGAUCUUUAACACUGAAGCAAUGGAGCUGGCCAACAGGCGUCUCUUGUCAGCACAAAUAGCAAGCUACCAGAGACAAUACAGGAAUGAGAUUCUGUCCCAGAGUGCUGUCCAGGUGUUGGUUGGUGCAGCAGAAAGUUUUGGUGAGAAGAAGGGAAAAUGUAUGAGUCUUGAUACAAUAAAGAAUUAUUCUGAAAGCCAAAAAACAGUUACCUUUGCUAGAAAACUACUACUUAAUUGGGUGUAUAAUACCAGAAAGGAAAAAGAGGGCCCAUCAAAAUACUUCUUUUUUCGUAUAUGCCAUACAAUAGUAUUUACUGAGGAAUUUGAACAUGUUGGAUACCUUGUGAUAUUAAUGAAUAUAUUUCCCUUUAUAAUCUCUUGGAUAUCCCAGUUAAAUGUAAUCUACCACAGCGAAUUAAAACACACUAACUACUGUUUUCUUACACUUUAUAUUCUAGAGGCACUACUUAAGAUAGCAGCAAUGAGGAAGGACUUUUUUUCACAUGCCUGGAACAUAUUCGAGUUAGCAAUUACAUUAAUUGGCAUCUUACAUGUAAUACUUAUUGAAAUAGACACCAUUAAGUAUAUUUUUAAUGAGACUGAAGUAAUAGUCUUUAUAAAAGUUGUUCAAUUUUUUCGUAUACUACGCAUUUUCAAGCUCAUAGCACCAAAGUUGCUGCAAAUAAUAGAUAAAAGAAUGAGUCAUCAGAAGACCUUUUGGUAUGGAAUACUAAAAGGCUAUGUCCAAGGCGAAGCAGACAUAAUGACCAUAAUUGAUCAGAUUACAAGUUCUAAACAGAUUAAACAGAUGUUAUUAAAGCAAGUGAUAAGGAAUAUGGAACAUGCUAUAAAAGAGCUAGGCUACUUAGAGUAUGAUCACCCAGAAAUUGCUGUCACUGUGAAAACAAAGGAAGAAAUUAAUGUUAUGCUCAAUAUGGCUACAGAAAUUCUUAAGGCUUUUGGCUUAAAAGGAAUUAUUAGUAAAACUGAAGGUGCUGGAAUUAAUAAGGAACAGACCACCUGUUUCUCUGCUUUGCUGUCAAACCAAAAGUCUGAUGAAUCUAUUCGUCAUCCUAGAUUACACACAGUAAUAGCUACUCCUCACCCCUCAGCACCAUGGCAGGCAGCUAUGCAUGUGUCCUUGGAGCAACUUACAACUUGCAAGAGCCAGAUUGGCAAUAAAAGACCCUGUUCUCUAAAUAUCUUGCAUCUGUACUCUGAUGACUGAUUGAUCGCUGUUUCUAAUCAGAGAAGGCAAAGAGGUGGAAACCAUUGUGAUUGCACCUCCUCACAUUAUUGUAAGCCCUCCCCCUCUGGCUGAAGUGACUUCCAAAGGAUUUAAAGGGCCAACACUUUUUUUAACCUCUUUAUUUUUGUCUUAUUUCUCUUUUGGGAGCCAGACUUUAGAGACUAAGACAUUCAAAAACCACCACUUCACAGGUGAAAUUAGAAAGUCACAAUGCAUGCACAGGGGAAGGCACAGGCUCAGAAAAAAAGUAAAAUAAAACCCUGACAAUGCCUUAAGCUUAGACCUAAGACUAAUCCUCAGCUCAGAGACAGACUACAACCACCAAAAAACAAAAACAAAACAGCAAAUUCUGGGGAAAAAGGGAGAGUCUGAGUUCCAGAAUUACCACAUUGUUUAAUUCAAAUUCAGUUUUUUUUUUUUAAAUCACAAGGCAUACACAAAAACUGGCAAGUAUUGCCCAUUCAAAAGAAAAAAAUAAAACAACAGAACUGUCCCUAAAAAAGAUGGCAGGUCUACCAGACAAAGACUUUAAAACAGUUGUUUUAAAGAUGCUCAAAGAACUCAAGGAAGAUGUGAGGAAAGUCAGGUAGAAAAUACAUGAACAAAAUGGAAAUAUCCAUAAAGACACAGAAAAUCUAAAAAGAAAUUCUGGAGCAGAAAAGUAAAAAGUACAAUUAAGUACAAUAACGAAAAUCUAAAAAUUUCCUAAGGGGAUUCAAAGGCAGAUUUGAGUAGGCAGAAAAAAGAAUCAGCAAACUUGAGGAUAGGUCACUGGAAAUUACAUGUCUGAGGAACAGAAAGAUAAAAAGAAUUUUUAAAAGUUAACAGAGCCUAAGGGGCCUGUGGGACACCUGAAGCAGACCAAUAUAUAUUGUGGGAGUCCAAGAGAGAGAAGGAAAAAAGACAAUAUUUGAGAAAAUAAUGGCCAAAAACUUUUGAAAUUUAAUGAAAGACAUGAAUGUAAACAUCCAAGAAUCUCAACAAAUUCCAAGUAGGAUGAACACAAACAGAACCACAUCUAGACACAUUAUAAUCAAACUGUUAAAAGACAAAAAGAAGUUUUAAGACAACAAGAGAGAAGCAAUCCAUCACACACAAGGAUCCUCAAUAAGAUUAAUAGCAGAUUUCUUACCCGAAAACUUGGAGGCCAGAAGCCAGUGAGCUGAUAUAUUCGAAGUGGAAAAAAAAAAAAGUGUCAGCCAAGAAUCUUACAUUCAGAAAAAUUGUACUUCAAAUGUAAAGGAAAAAUUGAGACAUUUCCAGAUAAACAAAAGUUUAGGGAGUUUGUUACCUCUAGAUCUGCCCUAAAAUAAAUGCAAAAGGAAGUCCUGCUGGUUAAAUGGAAGGACACUAGACAGUAACUCAGAACCUUAUAAAGAAAUAAGACUCAGUAAAGGUAAAUACAUAGGGAAUUAUAAAAGCUAGUAUUAUUGUAAUCAUGAUGUGUAACUCCACUUUUUGUUUUCUAAAUGAUUUACGAGAAUAAUAUUUCUACUAAAAACAGUUAUUAGUAUAAAACUAAUAUUAUUUUAACUUUGGAUUGCAUUAAAAAUAUUUCAUGUUUUUGGACACACAAUGUAUAAAGAUGUAAUACUGUGAUAUCAACAGCUGGAAGGAGAUGGGGAUGGAACUGUUGUUAAAGGAAUAGAGUUUUUGAAUGUUAUGGAAGUUAAGUUUGUAUAAAUUCAAAUUAUAGUGUUAUAGCUCUGGGAGUUCAUCUAUAAUGCCCAUGGUAAACACAUAAAAAAAGUAGCUAAAAUAUAUACACAGAAAUAAAUAAGAAAAUAACUUAAAUGUUUCACUAUUUUAAAAAAUCAACUUAACACAAAAGACAAUAAUAUAGGACAACAAAGCUACAGAUAUUUAGAAAAGCUAUACAAAAAAAAUACAGCAAAAUGACAGAAGUAAGUUCCUUCUUAUCAGUAAUUACUUUAAAUGUAAAGGGAUUAAACUCUCUAAUCAAAGACAGAGAUUGGCAGAACAGAUCAAAAAACAUGAUCCAACUAUGUGCUUUUUCUUUGAGAAACUGGAUCUCUACAUGCACAAGAAUAAAGUUGGACCCUUAACUAACAUCAUAUACAAAAAAUACCUCAAAAUAGACCCAUGACCUUUAUGUAAGACCUAAAACUAUAAAACUCUUAGAAGAAAACAUGGUUAAAACUUCAAAAUAUUGGAUUUGACAAUGAUUACUUGGAAAUGAUGCUUAAGGCACGUGCAGCAAAAUAAAAUAUAGACAAAGUGCACUUCAGGAAAAUUUGGAAAUUUUGUGUGUGCAUCAAAAACCACUAUUACAGAGUAAAACGACCCAAAGAAUGAGAGGAAAUAUUUGCAAACCAUUUGUCUUAUACAAAUUAAUACCCAUAAUAUAUAGAGAACUCAUAAAACUAAACAACCUGAUUCAAAAUGGGCAAAACAUUUGAAUAGAAAUUUCUCCAAAGAAGACACUCAAGUGGCCAAUAACAACAUGAAAAUAUAAUGAGUUUGACAUCAUUCAUCAUUAUGGAAAUGCAAAUCAAAACUACAGUGAGAUACCACCACACAUCCAUUAGGAUAGCUACCACCAAAAAAAAAAAAGAAAAUAUCAUUGUUUCGGUGAGGGUGUGGAGAAAUUGGAACCCUUGUACACUGUUGUUGGAAAAGUAAAAUGAUAUAACCUCUGUGGGAAACAGUAUGGCACUUUCUCAAAAAAGUUAAAAUUAGAAUUACCAUAUGAUCCAGUAAUUCCUUUUCUGGGUAUAUAGUCAAAAGAAUUGAAAGUGGAGUCUCAAGGAGUUAUUUGUACACCUACAUUCAUAGCAACAUUAUUCACAAUAACUAAAAUGUAGAAGCCAAUUAAUUUACAGUGACAUAGGCAAGAUGGCACACUAGAGGUGCCUGGUACUCAUUUCCUUCACCCCUGAAAAGAAAGGACCAAGGCAACAAAUUAAAAAAAUAAGAUUUGGCUGGAAUGUUGAGGGGAGAAAACUAAAGCACAGGCAGGGAGUAAAGAAGUACCUGUGGUGAUUGGAAAGCCCAGGAAGUCACAUGGAGUCACCCUGCUUCUGCAGCCCCAUCUCCCCCACGCAUAUUGGCCUGGAGUCAGAAAUAACUUCCCAUUUCAGGGAAAAGAUAGGCAGAAGAUUCCCACUGGCCCCCAAUGCCACCACAAGCACCUGCAGUCCUCCCUACAGAAGUAUCGCACAGUCUUUCCAAAACCUGAACAUUAUUUGGGGAGCUGCUGGGAAUUCAUGAAGCUGCAUUACUCCAGAUUAGGAUCAUAAGGUGUGCACGCCCCACUCCCUACCCAUCUACUGUGAGCCAAGCUGCUGCACCAUGGCACCAUCUUGACACCAGAGCCAUUUGUGGAGUGUACCCUGCUCAUGGGACCAGUUGCUAUUGCACCCCUCCAGCCCUGGAGCUGUCUCUUCAUUCCACCAAGCCCACAUGAAUGACUGAAUGCCACAAACCCAGUUGUGUGAAACUGGGGCCUAGGAUCAGCUGUGGCUCUGGUCCCACAUAGCAGGAAAACCAACCCCCACCACCCACAAUUCCAGCCAGAGAAACAGUCUUGCAGCCCCAUUCAGGACAAAACCUCUGUUGAAAUGGCCUAACCACUGUGUCUCUCCUGCAACCAGGAGAGGCCCACAAGCCAGCAAGUAGAUAACACACCCCCAGGCUAGCAGAGCAGCUACAAGUGUCCCCACCCAAGACCUGAAAAACAGCCCUGUCCCCACCAUUAACCUUAUGGACAUACCCCUGGCCUGCCCAAUGACCCCAUGCCAUCCCCAUACCCAGAGCCUGAGACACAACCCCAUGGGCUACCCCCAGCAGACAUAUUCCUAAGCCAGCAAAGCAGCCUUGUGCCUGUAUCCUGUGACCAAGAAAGAGCCCCAAGUUACCCUUCUCAACACAGACAUGCCUCUGGCCUGCUGAAUGCCCUGCACCAGAACUAAGGGCCUGAGAAACAGCCCCACAAGCCUCUGCUGAAAGAUAUGCCCCCAAUGUAGCUAAGCAGUCUUGUGCCCACAUGCCAGACCAGAAAAAAAGCCCAUCCAAUCCUAGGCAGACCUGCCUCCAAGCCAGCUAAAUAGUCGCAUGCCCAUGCCCCUGGCCAGAGUAACAGACCCAUGGCUCCAACCCUAGUGAUCCAGACCCCAGGUUAGCUGACAUGUCAUGUGCAUGCAUGUGCCCCCAACUUGAGAGGCAGUCCGGCAAGUCUAUACCUGGCAAAGCCAUGGCAUUACCACCACACGCUCUCAUAGCUUAGGCCACUGAAACACUUGCAAAAUUCACGAGUAUGGAUUCCAGUUGGAACAAACUACAUGGAGACUACACUACUGCAUCCACCUAGAUCCAAAGCCAAUGCAUUCUACCCAACCGACACCCCAAGACCUACUCAUGCCAAUAAGUCUUUCCCUAUGAAACCUACUUCAUAAAAUUCAAAGAGGCAAUUGUUCCACCAGAUGCAUAGAAAUUAGUGUAGUGACACAUCAAACAUGAAAAAGCAAGGAAAUAUGAUACUUCCAGGGGAACACAAUAACUCUCUACUAACAGAUACACAAAAUACCAGAAAAAAAUUUUAAAAUAAUCAUGUUAAGAAAACAGUAGGAUACAAGAGAAUACAGAUGGACAGUACACCAAAUCAGAAAAACAAUUCAUGAUUCAAGUGAGAAGUUUAACAAAGAACCAGACAGAAAUUCUAGAGCUGAGGAAUUCAAUGAAUGAAAUAAAAAACACAAUUGAGAGCUUCAAUAAAGACUAAACCAAGCAGAAAAAAUAAUUUCUGCACUUGAAGACAAGUCUUCUGAAAUAACUCAGGCAGACCAAAAAGAAAGAAAAAAACAAAAACAAAAAAAGAAUAGAAACAAUAAAAGGUAGACACCACCCAAGUGUCCAUUAAUAGAUGAAUGAAUGAGCAAAAUGUGGUAUAUACAUACAAUGGAAUUUUAUUUAACCUUAAAAAGAUAAAUCCUGAUAUAUACUACAAUAUAGAUGAAUCUUGAUGACUUGUGCUAAUUGAAAUAAGCCAGUCACAAAAAUCAAAUACUAUGUGAUUGCAUUUAUAUAAGGUAUUUAGAGAAUCAAAAGAUAGAGAAAUGAUGGAAUUGUAGUUGCCAGGGGCUGGGGAAGUUGAAAUGGGGAAUUAUUGUUUAAUGGGUAUAGAGUUUCAGUUGUGCAAGAUGAAAAGAAUUCUGGAGAUGGAUGGUAGUGAUGGUUAAGCAACAGUAUGAAUGUACUUAAUACCAGUGAAAAUGAAGGGAGCCUUAGCCAUUUAAAAUAGUUAAAAUAAUAAAUUUUUAUGUUACGUGUAUUUUACCACAGUAAAAAAAAAAAUGGAAAAAAACAGUGAGAGGGAUGUUUGCUCUACUAAAUAUUAAGACAUGCUAUAAAUCCAUAAUAAUCAAAUAGUGAAGAAUUAGAAUAGAAUAAAAAAAUUCAAGGAAAUAGAGUUGAGUCCAAUAGCAAACAUAAACACACAUGGUAGUCUAAUAUAUAAUAUUAAGGGACAUUGCAUAUUAGGAAGAAAUGAUAGAUUAUUCAAUAAAUAAUUCUGAGAUAUUUGAAAUUCAUAUGAAAAAAUAUAACAUUAGAUCCAUACCUCACACCAUAUAGAAAGAAAAACUUCCAGAUGCAAUGAUGAGUUAACAUUGCCAAACUCCUCCAAAAAAGCAAAGAAGGAAUACUUCCAAGCCCAUUUUAUGAGGCUAUCAUUAUUCUGAUAUCAAAGCCAGAUAAGGACAAGAAAAUUAUAGACCAAUAUUUCUGAUGAACAUACCUGCAAAUAUUCUCAACAAAAUAUUAACAAACUGAAUUCAAAAACACAUUGAAAGAAUCAUUCACCACAAUUGGUAAAGUGGGAUUUAUUUCUGAGAUGCAAGGACUGUUUGACAUACACAAAUCAAUAAAUGUGAUACACCACAUUAACAAAAUUAAGGAUAAAAUAAUAUGAUUUUCCCAAUUGAUAUAGAAAAGGCAUUUGACAAAAUUAAGCACCCUCUCAUAAUAAAAACUCUCAAUAGAUUAGGCAUAGAGAGAAUGUAUCUCAACGCAAUAAAGGCCAAAUAUGAUAAACCCAUUGCUCACAUCAUCCUCAAUGAGGAAAAGUUGAAAAAUCAGAGAGAAGAAAAGAAACGUCCUCUCUCCCCACUUAUUUUCAACAUAGUACUGGAAGUCCUGACCACAGCAGUUAGGCAUGAGAAGAAAUAAAAAGCAUCCUCAUAGGAAAGAAAGAAGUGAGACUGUCUCCAUUUUCUGAUGACAUGAUCUCAUAUAGAGAAAACCAUCAAAAACUUGUUAGAAUUGAUAAUUGAAUUUAGUAAAGUUGUAGGAUACAAAGUCAACUAUACAAAUGUUAUAAUGAAAUACAGAAUAUAUCUAUAUUCUUGAUGUGAGGAAAGCUUUUCUAAACCACUUACAAAGCCAUAUAUAUAUAUGUGUGUGUGUGUGUGUGUGUGUGUGUGUGUGUGUGUUUAAAAAAAGUAAAAAUUACUGCAUAAAAUUUAAAACUUUAUAUAUUGAAAUAUAUUAAAAUGAGAUUAAAAGCAAACAUGGAAAAUAACAUUUGUAACAUGUAUUACACACAAAGUACUGAUAGCAAUAAUUCCUAAAAAGUUUAUAGAAAUCAAUUUAAAAAGGGCAAAAAAUCCUGGAGAAAGUGAAAAAAGGGUAUUAAAAAGUAUUUCACAGAUAUAUAAACAAAAUUUACAAUGAAUGUUUGAAAAGAUAUUUGACAUCCCUAAUAAUCAAAGAAUAGAAGUAUUUUCUUUAGUAAAUAGAAACUAGAGAAAUAAAACUAAAGAUACAAUUUUUUUGCCAAUUAAAUCAGAAAUGAUGGGCAAAAACUGUUAUUGUUCAAUGCUAAUUAGGUUAUGAGAAAAUAGACUUAAAUAUGGUAGACUAAAAUGUAAGUCAGCACAGCCAUUCUGGAGGGCAAUUUAGAAAAUUCAACGGCCAUUCAUGCUAAAAACUCUCAAUAAACUAGGUAUUGAUGGAAUGUAUCUCAAAAUAAUAAGAGCUAUUU